AGGCGGUCGCCGGGACACCCCGUGUGUGGCAGGCGGCGAAGCGCUCUGGAGAAUCCCGGACAGCCCUGCUCCCUGCAGCCAGGUGUAGUUUCGGGAGCCACUGGGGCCAAAGUGAGAGUCCAGCGGUCUUCCAGCGCUUGGGCCACGGCGGCGGCCCUGGGAGCAGAGGUGGAGCGACCCCAUUACGCUAAAGAUGAAAGGCUGGGGUUGGCUGGCCCUGCUUCUGGGGGCCCUGCUGGGAACCGCCUGGGCUCGGAGGAGCCAGGAUCUCCACUGUGGAGCAUGCAGGGCUCUGGUGGAUGAACUAGAAUGGGAAAUUGCCCAGGUGGACCCCAAGAAGACCAUUCAGAUGGGAUCUUUCCGGAUCAAUCCAGAUGGCAGCCAGUCAGUGGUGGAGGUGCCUUAUGCCCGCUCAGAGGCCCACCUCACAGAGCUGCUGGAGGAGAUAUGUGACCGGAUGAAGGAGUAUGGGGAACAGAUUGAUCCUUCCACCCAUCGCAAGAACUACGUACGUGUAGUGGGCCGGAAUGGAGAAUCCAGUGAACUGGACCUACAAGGCAUCCGAAUCGACUCAGAUAUUAGCGGCACCCUCAAGUUUGCGUGUGAGAGCAUUGUGGAGGAAUACGAGGAUGAACUCAUUGAAUUCUUUUCCCGAGAGGCUGACAAUGUUAAAGACAAACUUUGCAGUAAGCGAACAGAUCUUUGUGACCAUGCCCUGCACAUAUCGCAUGAUGAGCUAUGAACCACUGGAGCAGCCCACACUGGCUUGAUGGAUCACCCCCAGGAGGGGAAAAUGGUGGCAAUGCCUUUUAUAUAUUAUGUUUUUACUGAAAUUAACUGAAAAAAUAUGAAACCAAAAGUACAAACUGUGUUGUCUUUUCAUGCCUGGAAUUGCCCUUACAUUAAGCUUGAAGAUAAGGAGUUAUAUAGACAGGAAAGAUAAUGGAGGAGAAAGAAGAGUUUUGGGAUUGAUACAGGAUAAAGGUAGGAGAGGCCUGAACCUUUAAUUCUUCUACCUUCUGAGAUUCCACUCCACUCAUAAACUAGAUAAGCUUUCAGUCAGUGCCCACUCAAUACCACGUCUUUAGAGUCUAAUUGUGGAGAAUAGAGGAACCUCCAUGAGGAAGCAGGGGAACAUAGUGUAUGGUAGUGUAGAAUUCUAGAAAUCCCUUGUGUUCAUGGCUGUUGAAACAUAAAGUAAGACAGGGCUUGGUCUUGAAGGAAAUAACGGAUAUGCAUUAUUCUUCCUUCCCUGCCCAUCCAGAUGGAGGGACCAGCAAGAACAGAGACAGGAAGGGGAAAAUGGAUGUGACCAACUCAGCUGAAAAGUAAGGGCUUUAUCGGAUAGGGACAGACGAGGUAAGGAAGGUUGUUUAAUGAGAGGCCUUGCUUGCCAGCCUAAGCUUUUAAAUUUGAUGCCAGUGGCAACAAUAAAGUGUAUCUAUCACUA